ACUUCUCGCUCGACACAGCCAGAGCUGGAGGUGGGUGCCCGGCACGGAGGGGCCUGCGGACCAAUGGCUCUGCCCUGCACCUUAGGGCUCGGGAUGCUGCUGGCCCUGCCAGGGGCCUUGGGCUCGGGUGGCAGCGCGGAGGACAGCGUGGGCUCCAGCUCUGUCACCGUUGUCCUGCUGCUGCUGCUGCUCCUACUGCUGGCCACUGGCCUAGCACUGGCCUGGCGCCGCCUCAGCCGUGACUCAGGGGGCUACUACCACCCGGCCCGCCUAGGUGCCGCGCUGUGGGGCCGCACGCGGCGCCUGCUCUGGGCCAGCCCCCCAGGUCGCUGGCUGCAGGCCCGAGCUGAGCUGGGGUCCACAGACAAUGACCUUGAGCGACAGGAGGAUGAGCAGGACACAGACUAUGACCACGUCGCGGAUGGUGGCCUGCAGGCUGACCCUGGGGAAGGCGAGCAGCAAUGUGGAGAGGCGUCCAGCCCAGAGCAGGUCCCCGUGCGGGCUGAGGAAGCCAGAGACAGUGACACGGAGGGCGACCUGGUCCUCGGCUCCCCAGGACCAGCGAGCGCAGGGGGCAGUGCUGAGGCCCUGCUGAGUGACCUGCACGCCUUUGCUGGCAGCGCAGCCUGGGAUGACAGCGCCAGGGCAGCUGGGGGCCAGGGCCUCCAUGUCACCGCACUGUAGAGGCCGGUCUUGGUGUCCCAUCCCUGUCACAGCCGCUCACUCCCCGUGCCUCUGCUUCCCAAGAUGCCAUGGCUGGACUGGACCCCCAGCCCACAUGACCAUGCCUCAGACUGUCACCCCCUACCAGUUCCCAAGUCCAUGUGUACCCCGCUCACCACGGGAACGGCCCCCCCCAACCACAGGCAUCAGGCAACCAUUUGAAAUAAAACUCCUUCAGCCUGUG